AACUGAAGGUAAUCUCCUUUAAAGUCAACAUCUUGUAGCUAUUAAUCACGUCUAUUAGACGUCUAAUAGACGUGAUUAAUAGCUACAAGUAUAUAAUAGCUUCACAGCACUAUCUAGGCUAGAUUUUGACCAAACACCUGGACACUAUAGCCUCACAAAAUUGACACAUAAAAUGUAACCAUCACUGACUGCAUCAACCCAAGAGGCUAACAGUGAAAUAAGACCAUGACAAGCUAAUUUUCACAUGUUGAAGGAAAGCCCAACAGAGACACUCUAUAAAGUUAGAGGGGUGACUGAAGAGACCUCAACUCUGGUUCUUGGGGGCUCUGGUCCCUGGGGCCAGAGUGACUGAGCCAGGAUUACAGUCUGAAGCAUUAGAGGAGGGGUGGGGGUAGGCCCCCCAUUGUGAGGUCCAGGCAGAAUGCUCAACUCACAGCGAUCCCAGCCCUGGCUGACCUUCUUCCCCUUCCUCAUUCCCACAUUCUACCAGGAGUCUGUCCUCUGGCCUGUACCUGGACUUCGCUAUCCUCUCCCUGCCCCAAAAAGAGGUUUGAGGGAGAACAGCCACAGAGCCAAUGGAGGCCACGAGGACACGGCCUCACUCAGUACUCAAGGUGUCUUCCUGCCCCCGUCCCCAGCAGUGGCAAACGAACGAGUCCUCGAAGAAGUGGGGAUCAUGGCCUUGGCACCCCUGGCCGAGAUGCUAACCAGCUUGCAGCCCAGCGCCACACCGGGCUCACUCAUGAGCCCCCUGACAGGCACCCUCAGCACGCUGCUGUCUGGCCCAGCACCCACGUCACAGAGCAGCCCCCUCACCAGCUUCCUGACCAGUCCCAUUGCGGGACCCCUAACAGGCACACUGGCCAGUUCCCUGGGCCUGCCCUCCACUGGCACCCUGACUCCCAGCAGCCUCGUGGCAGGCCCUGUGGCCAUGUCCCAGAGCAGCCCCCUGAUAGCCCCUGUGAUGGGCACGGUGGCUGUCUCUCUGAGCAGCCCCCUCCUCAGCUCCACUGCCACCCCACCAGGGGUCUCUCAGAACCUGCUGGCCAACCCCAUGAGCAACCUGGUCCUGCCAGAGGCCCCAAGGCUGCGGCUGGCUGAGCCACUCCGCGGAGGCCCCACUGGGCCCCAGUCCCCAGCUUGCGUGGUACCCACUGCCACCACCAAAGUCCCACUCUCCACUGAGCCCCCCCAGUCGACCCAGGACCCAGAGCCUCUCAGCAUGGCGUUUGCAGGAGCACCCCUCCAGACCUCCACCCCUAUCGGAGCCAUGGGCACACCUGCUCCCAAGACGGCCUUCUCCUUCAACACUUCGGACACACAGGCCCAGCCCAGUGCCGCCCAGGAACAAGUGGUCCCUGCAUCUGUCCCCACCUCCCCCACCACCUCCCCCACGGUCACCGUCCUUGCCUCUGCCCCCGCCCUUGCCCCCCAGGUUGCCACCAGCUACACACCCUCAAGCACCACCCACAUCGCCCAGGGUGCCCCCCAUCCCCCUUCCCGAAUGCAUAAUUCCCCAACCCAGAACCUGCCUGUCCCCCACUGUCCUCCACACAACGCCCACUCCCCACCUCGUACCUCAUCCUCCCCGGCUUCAGUCAAUGACUCUCGAGGUCCACGCACCACAGAACCGUCGACGAAGAGCAUGAUGGAGGUGGAACGGAAGCUGGCCCACCGCAAGACCAGCAAGUUCCCCGAGAACCCCCGAGAGUCGAAGCAGCUGGCCUGGGAGAGGCUGGUGGGUGAGAUUGCCUUCCAGCUGGACCGCAGGAUCCUGUCCAGCAUCUUCCCAGAGCGCGUACGGCUCUACGGCUUCACUGUCUCCAACAUCCCAGAGAAGAUCAUCCAGCUGUGUUUAUCUGUGGAUUGCAGGCCUGUGUGUAGCCUAAGCGGGAGCUACUGUGAGCUGCGUGGGUCCAGGUUGGAGCUUUGCCUCUGGUUAAAGCAUCCUUGGGCUUCCCUGAACCCCAGUGACCACAAGCUGGAUGAGAAGCUGUGCCAGAGGCUCACACAGCGCUAUGUGAGCGUCAUGAACAGGCUGCAGAGUCUGGGCUACAACGGGCGGGUGCACCCUGCGCUGACCGAGCAGCUGGUGAACGCUUAUGGCAUCCUGCGAGAGCGCCCGGAGCUGGCGGCGUCUGAGGGCGGCCCCUACACCGUGGACUUCCUGCAGCGUGUGGUGGUGGAGACCGUGCACCCCGGCAUGCUCGCCGACGCGCUGCUGCUGCUCUCCUGCCUCAGCCAGCUGGCGCACGAUGACGGCAAGCCCAUGUUCAUCUGGUGACGCUGGAGCUGGGAGGUCCAGGCUCGCUCAGCCCCACAGCCCUGUGCACGGCCAUUAAAGCUUCCCACAGACACUGGUCGCUGGGCCUGUGCCAGCGCUCCUGGGUGGUGCUGCCUCCUCUGGGGUGGCUCACCGGGCCCCGGCACCGUGCCCCUUCA